GGUUCGGUAUCGCGAGUAUGGCCGUUGGGAGGCAGCGAAAGGGCCCAGGCCCUCCUGGAAGACAGUGGAGUCCUGAGGGGACCCAGCAUGCCAGGACAGGGGGCCCACUGUACCCCUGUCUCAAACCGAGGCACCUUUUCAUUCGGCUACGGGAAUCCUAGGGAUGCAGACCCACUUCAGCAGGGGGUUGGGGCCCAGCCCUGCGAGGAGUCAUGGGGAGGAAGAAGAGGGAGGACUGAGGGGACCUUGGAGUCCAGAUCAGUGGCAACCUUGGGCUGGGGGAUGCUGGGCACAGUGGCCAAAUGUGCUCUGUGCUCAUUGCGCCUUCAGGGUGACCAGAGAGUUGAGGGCUGUGGUCUGAAGAGUGGGACUUCAGGUCAGCAGAGGGAGGAAUCCCAGGAUCUGCAGGGCCCAAGGUGUACCCCCAAGGGGCCCCUAUGUGGUGGACAGAUGCAGUGGUCCUAGGAUCUGCCAAGCAUCCAGGUUCUGAGGGGACAGGCUGACCUGGAGGACCAGAGGCCCCCGGAGGAGCACUGAAGGAGAAGAUCUGCCAGUGGGUCUCCAUUGCCCAGCUCCUGCCCACACUCCCGCCUGUUGCCCUGACCAGAGUCAUCAUGCCUCUUGAGCAGAGGAGUCAGCACUGCAAGCCUGAAGAAGGCCUUGAGGCCCGAGGAGAGGCCCUGGGCCUGGUGGGUGCGCAGGCUCCUGCUACUGAGGAGCAGGAGGCUGCCUCCUCCUCUUCUACUCUAGUUGAAGUCACCCUGGGGGAGGUGCCUGCUGCCGAGUCACCAGAUCCUCCCCAGAGUCCUCAGGGAGCCUCCAGCCUCCCCACUACCAUGAACUACCCUCUCUGGAGCCAAUCCUAUGAGGACUCCAGCAACCAAGAAGAGGAGGGGCCAAGCACCUUCCCUGACCUGGAGUCCGAGUUCCAAGCAGCACUCAGUAGGAAGGUGGCCGAGUUGGUUCAUUUUCUGCUCCUCAAGUAUCGAGCCAGGGAGCCGGUCACAAAGGCAGAAAUGCUGGGGAGUGUCGUCGGAAAUUGGCAGUAUUUCUUUCCUGUGAUCUUCAGCAAAGCUUCCAGUUCCUUGCAGCUGGUCUUUGGCAUCGAGCUGAUGGAAGUGGACCCCAUCGGCCACUUGUACAUCUUUGCCACCUGCCUGGGCCUCUCCUACGAUGGCCUGCUGGGUGACAAUCAGAUCAUGCCCAAGGCAGGCCUCCUGAUAAUCGUCCUGGCCAUAAUCGCAAGAGAGGGCGACUGUGCCCCUGAGGAGAAAAUCUGGGAGGAGCUGAGUGUGUUAGAGGUGUUUGAGGGGAGGGAAGACAGUAUCUUGGGGGAUCCCAAGAAGCUGCUCACCCAACAUUUCGUGCAGGAAAACUACCUGGAGUACCGGCAGGUCCCCGGCAGUGAUCCUGCAUGUUAUGAAUUCCUGUGGGGUCCAAGGGCCCUCGUUGAAACCAGCUAUGUGAAAGUCCUGCACCAUAUGGUAAAGAUCAGUGGAGGACCUCACAUUUCCUACCCACCCCUGCAUGAGUGGGUUUUGAGAGAGGGGGAAGAGUGAGUCUGAGCACGAGUUGCAGCCAGGGCCAGUGGGAGGGGGUCUGGGCCAGUGCACCUUCCGGGGCCGCAUCCCUUAGUUUCCACUGCCUCCUGUGACGUGAGGCCCAUUCUUCACUCUUUGAAGCGAGCAGUCAGCAUUCUUAGUAGUGGGUUUCUGUUCUGUUGGAUGACUUUGAGAUUAUUCUUUGUUUCCUGUUGGAGUUGUUCAAAUGUUCCUUUUAACGGAUGGUUGAAUGAGCGUCAGCAUCCAGGUUUAUGAAUGACAGUAGUCACACAUAGUGCUGUUUAUAUAGUUUAGGAGUAAGAGUCUUGUUUUUUACUCAAAUUGGGAAAUCCAUUCCAUUUUGUGAAUUGUGACAUAAUAAUAGCAGUGGUAAAAGUAUUUGCUUAAAAUUGUGAGCGAAUUAGCAAUAACAUACAUGAGAUAACUCAAGAAAUCAAAAGAUAGUUGAUUCUUGCCUUGUACCUCAAUCUAUUCUGUAAAAUUAAACAAAUAUGCAAACCAGGAUUUCCUUGACUUCUUUGAGAAUGCAAGCGAAAUUAAAUCUGAAUAAAUAAUUCUUCCUCUUCA